GUCUUCUGUCUCCGCCUCACCCUCAGGCCUGACGGUCCGAGUGGAGCUGCGGGACAGCCCGAACCUCCAGGUCAGCCCCGCGGCCCUCCAUGGCGCUGGUGCGCGCACUCGUCUGCUGCCUGCUGACUGCCUGGCACUGCCGCUCCGGCCUCGGGCUGCCCGUGGCGCCCGCAGGCGGCAGGAAUCCUCCUCCGGCGAUAGGACAGUUUUGGCAUGUGACUGACUUACACUUAGACCCUACUUACCACAUCACAGAUGACCACACAAAAGUGUGUGCUUCAUCUAAAGGUGCAAAUGCCUCCAACCCUGGCCCUUUUGGAGAUGUUCUGUGUGAUUCUCCAUAUCAACUUAUUUUGUCAGCAUUUGAUUUUAUUAAAAAUUCUGGACAAGAAGCAUCUUUCAUGAUAUGGACAGGGGAUAGCCCACCUCAUGUUCCUGUACCUGAACUCUCAACAGACACUGUUAUAAAUGUGAUCACUAAUAUGACAACCACCAUCCAGAGUCUCUUUCCAAAUCUCCAGGUUUUCCCUGCGCUGGGUAAUCAUGACUAUUGGCCACAGGAUCAACUGCCUGUAGUCACCAGUAAAGUGUACAAUGCAGUAGCAAACCUCUGGAAACCAUGGCUAGAUGAAGAAGCUAUUAGUACUUUAAGGAAAGGUGGUUUUUAUUCACAGAAAGUUACAACUAAUCCAAACCUUAGGAUCAUCAGUCUAAACACAAACUUGUACUACGGCCCAAAUAUAAUGACACUGAACAAGACUGACCCAGCCAACCAGUUUGAAUGGCUAGAAAGUACAUUGAACAACUCUCAGCAGAAUAAGGAGAAGGUGUAUAUCAUAGCACAUGUUCCAGUGGGGUAUCUGCCAUCUUCACAGAACAUCACAGCAAUGAGAGAAUACUAUAAUGAGAAAUUGAUAGAUAUUUUUCAAAAAUACAGUGAUGUCAUUGCAGGACAAUUUUAUGGACACACUCACAGAGACAGCAUUAUGGUUCUUUCAGAUAAAAAAGGAAGUCCAGUAAAUUCUUUGUUUGUGGCUCCUGCUGUUACACCAGUGAAGAGUGUUUUAGAAAAACAGACCAACAAUCCUGGUAUCAGACUGUUUCAGUAUGAUCCUCGUGAUUAUAAAUUAUUGGAUAUGUUGCAGUAUUACUUGAAUCUGACAGAGGCGAAUCUAAAGGGAGAGUCCAUCUGGAAGCUGGAGUAUAUCCUGACCCAGACCUACGACAUUGAAGAUUUGCAGCCGGAAAGUUUAUAUGGAUUAGCUAAACAAUUUACAAUCCUAGACAGUAAGCAGUUUAUAAAAUACUACAAUUACUUCUUUGUGAGUUAUGACAGCAGUGUAACAUGUGAUAAGACAUGUAAGGCCUUUCAGAUUUGUGCAAUUAUGAAUCUUGAUAAUAUUUCCUAUGCAGAUUGCCUCAAACAGCUUUAUAUAAAGCACAAUUACUAGUAUUUCACAGUUUUUGCUAAUAGAAAAUGCUGAUUCUGAUUCUGAGAUCAAUUUGUGGGAAUUUUACAUAAAUCUUUGUUAAUUACUGAGUGGGCAAGUAGACUUCCUGUCUUUGCUUUCUUUUUUUUUUUCUUUUUGAUGCCUUAAUGUAGAUAUCUUUAUCAUUCUGAAUUGUAUUAUAUAUUUAAAGUGCUCAUUAAUAGAAUGAUGGAUGUAAAUUGGAUGUAAAUAUUCAGUUUAUAUAAUUAUAUCUAAUUUGUACCCUUGUUGAAAUUGUCAUUUAUACAAUAAAGCGAAUUCUUUAUCUCUAAA